AGUUUGUGCUCGGGCUCUGAACACCGCCGGCCGGACCGCGGGCUGCGUCACGGGGACCGGGAGGCGUACGGCGACGCGGAGCAGCGCCUUUGCGGCGUGCGACCCGCCCCCGCCGUCCCUCCCUCCCUCCCCUCAGGGCUUCGGGCCCCCGGGGCCAGCCGCCGUCCUGCGAACGCGCGGCGCCCGGGCCGCUGCCCCCUUCCGGCCCCGCGGCGGCCCCGCCUCCUCCCCCGACUUCCUUCCCUGAGCACGGCGGCGGCGGGGACGAGCACCGGCCUGCGCGCGGAGCCGGCACCGGAUGGUGGGCGGGGGCCAGCCGUGCGGGUACGCGGCCCGCGCGCCCCUAGCCACCGCCGCGUGGCACCGUCCCGAGCGCGUGGCGCGGGGCGCUGGCUGCCGGGCGGGGGCCUGGGGCCGCGGACGCUGGGGGCGCCUCGGCCGCGCUCAGCCUUUAGAUCGGAGAAUGCGGGCGGGGUGGGGGCGCUCGGGGUCCCCGCAGUCACUCCAGGGUCGAUUUCUCGGCGGGCGCCGCGGCCUGUGCGAGGCCGGGCCCCUUGGAGUGCCCCGGGAGGUGGUGCUGGGCGUCUGAACACCACAUCCCUUCCUGCGCCCGUGUGUGGGUUGGGAAUGCCGGGUGUAGGCCCUGGAUCAGAGCUGACGGGGUUGCGAGCGGCGUGGGGUGUGCCUGGGACGGUGACCGGAUGUGUCUUCCUGAAUCGUUGUAUUCGAGCUCCAGUUCUCUCUGUUUCUACAGCUGGGCCUCAGUCCUCACAGGGCUCUAGUGGGCGUUCAGCCACACCAGGAGAAGGCGCCCAGGGGAUUAACAGGACCCUUCCCUCUCCUGCUCUUCCCUCGCCCCCCAUGGCUCCCCCUCCCUCCUAUUUAGUAGGUACUUCUCCAGCACCCCACAGCGAUGAUGGAUGCUGGCCCUAAAGCCAGGCACUGCCGCCCUGCACUGUAGCAGAUGCCUAAAUAAAGUGUGGAGCCUGAAGCAGAAGUUUUGGGAGAUGCUUGCCUUCCUUUAGACCACAUUCCUCGCCUUUCUCAAGAUUUCUCCGUGGUACCCACCCCGUUUUUGUGUUGUCUUCCUUCCUUGCCCUUGUUUCAUUCCUUUUGAAAGCGACCACUCCCCUGAAGUCCUAGGACCCCCUUCGUGGGCUCUCCCUGCCGUAGACAGUCUCUGCUUGCCCCUGGGAGACAGACCCAACAUGAGUGAAGUUUCCUGCAAGAAACGGGACGACUAUUUGGAAUGGCCAGAGUAUUUUAUGGCUGUGGCCUUCUUAUCAGCACAGAGAAGCAAAGAUCCAAAUUCCCAGGUCGGCGCCUGCAUCGUGAAUUCAGAAAACAAGAUUGUCGGGAUUGGGUACAAUGGGAUGCCAAAUGGGUGCAGUGAUGACGUGUUGCCUUGGAGAAGGACAGCAGAGAAUAAGCUGGACACCAAAUACCCGUACGUGUGCCAUGCGGAGCUGAAUGCCAUCAUGAACAAAAAUUCGACCGAUGUGAAAGGCUGUAGUAUGUAUGUUGCCUUGUUCCCUUGUAAUGAAUGCGCUAAGCUCAUCAUCCAGGCAGGUAUAAAAGAAGUGAUUUUCAUGUCUGAUAAAUACCAUGAUAGUGACGAGGCAACUGCUGCGAGGCUCCUGUUUAAUAUGGCCGGGGUGACAUUCCGGAAAUUCAUACCGAAGUGCAGCAAGAUUGUCAUUGACUUUGAUUCAAUUAACAGCAGACCGAGUCAAAAGCUUCAGUGAGUUACAUCUCAUUCAAUCUCCAGAAGAUUGGGAUUAUCGUCUUCUAAGAGGUUGCUAAUGCCUUUCAUCUUGAAGUUACACAUAACUUCUUACUAGCCAGUAUGGCAAAAGUAGGCAUCUAAAGAAUAUAAAGCCUCAAAUCUUCCUUACUGUCUCUCUUGUCACAUGGAAUCUACAUGUGUUUGAACUAUUGCUUUAGGGUUUAAAAUAGGGGAGCCUGUGGUGGCCUGGUGCACAGGGCUAGAACGAGAGUGCCUCCCCUUCUUGUGUCCUGGCUGGCUGGGAUGCUGGUGGCUCUUCAGAGGAGCAUCAGCUGUCUGUCAUCUGCUGCGAUCCGGCAGCCUCUCUUCACUGCUACAUGUGCUGGAAGGACAAAUAAAUAAUUGUGGUUGUGUUCUUAAUGGGGACGAGCAGACACACUGAUCUGAACAUCUGGCCCAAGUGAAGCAUGGCAUAUAGUGCCCUUGGAAGAAAAUUAGGCCUCAAAUGACAGUAGCAUUGAAGUGUUUGCUGCAGAGUUGAGGGAAACCCCCAGCCACCCUCCCGGAAUCCGAGAUAGGGUGGCACAUCUGUCCUGACAGACGAGGAGUGUAACUGAACCAGGAAUAUUUCCUCCAUUCCUGCUCUCCCACUGCACACAGGGUGGUGGCACAUUAUCCCUCUGGGGGGUGGGGACGCCUGUUGUUUUGGCUCAAUUUGGGUUUGUUGGUCACAUGGAGCUCUUCCAUUUCGUUUAGCUGAAUAAUGAGUUGUUCCUAGAGGAGACAGCCUGUCUCUCCUUGUUGCCCCCAAAGCCCAUGCCCUGCCGUGGUGGCAGCUGGGGCUGUGGAUGGGAGGGGUCCCCAACAUGGAUGUGUUGCCCCUCCUCCGCAUGCCAACGCAGUUCAUGUACAAGGCCCCUCUGCAACUGGAGAGAAAAUUAAUUCCUAUCCCGUGAGUGGAUUGUGAGAAAUUCCACCCACGUGGAGACAGCUUACUGCAGCACUGUUGGUGUUCGGAGCUCUUCUGUGCCCUGGCUCCAUGCUUUCACCUACACAAGCAUCACCUUCCUAAUCACCGCGGGGCGGGGAGCGUGUGGCUGUGCCCCUUCUCUUUAAUCUCAUUUAAUUUUUAUUAAACAUGCUCAGUACCUGUGUUGAGAAAAGGCUUUCUUUAUCCUAAAGAUUAUUACCUUUUUAAAGUGCUCUUAUAUUUUCAUGAGUUUUUAUUUUGUCUCUGAGAUUUUGUAUUCCACAUUCUAGGGUAUUCUGUAAUUUGGCUCCUUACCAAUAUUAUUAAAAUCUUAUUAAAAUCUACCCUACCAAAGCA